GCCGCCGCCGCCUCGGCCGCCGAGGAGCCGCCGCCGCCGUCGCCGCCGCCGCCGAGCCGCAGCCAGAGUCGCUGCCGCCGCCCGGCCCGGCCCGGCCCGGCCCCGAGCAGCCCCGCGCCGCCGCCGCCCCGCCCGCCCGGCCCCCCGUGCCCGCCCCCGCCGCUGGAUGCAGGCGGCCGGCGGCCCAGCUCGCAGAGGCGGAGGGCGGCGCGGGCGGCGGCGGCGGCGCGGGCGGCAGGAGCGCGGGCCCCAGCGCUAGCUCCCGCCAUGCCCAGCUCGCUCGGCCAGCCCGACGGCGGCGGGGGCGGGGGCGGCGGCGGCGGCGGCGUGGGGGCGGCGGGGGAGGACCCCGGACCCGGACCUGCGCCCCCGCCCGAGGGCGCCCAGGAGGCCGCGCCCGCGCCCCGGCCGCCGCCCGAACCCGACGACGCGGCCGCCGCGCUCCGCCUGGCGCUGGACCAGCUGUCGGCGCUCGGGCUGGGGGGCGCUGGCGACACGGACGAGGAGGGGGCGGCCGGGGACGGCGCAGCGGCGGCGGGGGGCGCGGACGGCGGGGCGGCUCCGGAGCCUGUGCCCCCCGACGGACCUGAGGCCGGCGCGCCCCCGACCCUGGCCCCCGCCGUGGCCCCCGGGUCGCUGCCGCUGCUGGACCCCAACGCGAGUCCCCCGCCGCCGCCGCCGCCCCGGCCGUCGCCCCCCGACGUGUUCGCGGGCUUCGCGCCCCACCCCGCGGCCCUGGGGCCCCCGACGCUGCUGGCCGACCAGAUGAGCGUGAUCGGCAGCCGCAAGAAAAGCGUCAACAUGACCGAGUGCGUCCCGGUGCCCAGCUCCGAGCACGUCGCCGAGAUCGUGGGUCGCCAGGGCUGCAAGAUCAAGGCCCUGCGGGCCAAGACAAACACCUACAUCAAGACCCCAGUGCGGGGCGAGGAGCCGGUCUUCAUCGUGACCGGCCGGAAGGAGGACGUGGAGAUGGCCAAGCGUGAGAUCCUGUCGGCGGCCGAACACUUCUCCAUCAUCCGCGCCACGCGCAGCAAGGCCGGGGGUCUGCCCGGCGCCGCCCAGGGCCCGCCCAACCUUCCCGGACAGACCACCAUCCAGGUGCGCGUGCCCUACCGGGUGGUGGGGCUGGUGGUGGGGCCCAAGGGCGCCACCAUCAAGCGCAUCCAGCAGCGGACGCACACCUACAUCGUGACGCCCGGGCGCGACAAGGAGCCGGUGUUCGCGGUCACUGGGAUGCCCGAGAACGUGGACCGCGCGCGCGAGGAGAUCGAGGCGCACAUCACGCUGCGCACUGGCGCCUUCACCGACGCGGGCCCCGACAGCGACUUCCACGCCAACGGCACCGACGUCUGCCUGGACCUGCUCGGGGCGGCCGCCAGCCUCUGGGCCAAGACCCCCAACCAGGGACGACGGCCCCCCACGGCCACGGCCGGCCUCCGCGGGGACACGGCCCUGGGCGCCCCCAGCGCCCCCGAGGCCUUCUACGCGGGCAGCCGCGGCGGCCCCUCCGUGCCGGACCCAGGCCCCGCCAGCCCCUACAGCGGCUCCGGCAACGGGGGCUUCGCCUUCGGCGCGGAGGGUCCCGGUGCCCCGGUGGGGACGGCCGCCCCCGACGACUGCGACUUCGGCUUCGACUUCGACUUCCUGGCGCUGGACCUGACCGUGCCCGCCGCGGCCACCAUCUGGGCGCCUUUUGAGCGCGCCGCCCCCUUGCCCGCCUUCAGCGGCUGCUCCACGGUCAACGGAGCCCCGGGACCUCCCGCCGCCGGCGCCCGGCGCAGCAGUGGGGCCGGGACCCCCCGCCACUCGCCCACGCUGCCCGAGCCCGGCGGCCUCCGCCUGGAGCUCCCGCUGUCUCGCCGUGGCGCCCCGGACCCGGUGGGCGCGCUGUCCUGGCGACCCCCGCAGGGCCCCGUAUCCUUCCCAGGCGGCGCCGCCUUCUCCACGGCCACCUCGCUGCCCAGCAGCCCCGCGGCCGCCGCCUGCGCCCCCCUGGACUCCGGCGCCUCCGAGAACAGCCGCAAGCCCCCUUCGGCGUCCUCGGCCCCGGCCCUGGCGCGAGAGUGCGUGGUGUGCGCCGAGGGCGAGGUGAUGGCUGCGCUGGUCCCCUGCGGCCACAACCUCUUCUGCAUGGACUGCGCCGUCCGCAUCUGCGGCAAGAGCGAGCCCGAGUGUCCCGCCUGCCGCACGCCGGCCACCCAGGCCAUUCAUAUCUUUUCCUAGAGCGCGGACCACCACGUGGCCGGGGCCAUCUGCGGGGGCCAGGGGUGGGCGCGGGAGACGGGGCGGGACCCGGGGUGGGAGAGGGACGGGGAGGGGGCGAGGGGCGGAGGCCGAGGGGGCAGGGGGGUGGGCGGCGGCCAGUGUUUACAGAUGAGCUUUAACUGCCGCCUCAGGCGUGGAGACGGAGACCCCGCAGCCCGGCGGCGCCUCAGCCCUUCAACGACAGUAUUGAGUGGUCAGGUUACAAUAAACCGGAGAGAAAAGGUCCGCUUGCACUUUUUUUAGUUUUCUUAUUUUUAGACACCCCUCCCCUCCAGGGUGAUCUUUAAAAAAGCAAAACAAAAAACACGACUUUUCCAGCGCUCAGCGUUUUUUCCUUUCGUCCGAAGCCGUUUUCUGAUUUGACUUUUCUCGCCGGCCGGUCUCAGGCCGCACAGACGUUCCAGAGGAGGAGGGUGACAUUUUUACUCCCUUUUUGGGGCUAACCAUUUAUGCUUUUGUACAUCAACCGUGCGCGGCCGGAGGGGGCAGGGGGGCGGGGGCGAGGGGCGUUCCAAUCAAAUUUCUAACUUUCUGUUAAUUAUUAAUCCCCUUUUUACUGCGGUUUCUGUUGUCAUUUUUAAAAUUUUUUUAAUUUUUUUUUUUUUUUACUUUUACUUUUUACCUCUUGUGUAUAUGUAGGGAAUUUAUAGGGAAAUAUGUACUUUAUGGAAUAAAUUUUAAGAACUAAAAUAUAUUUUAUUUUAAAUAAAGUAAUGGACCUUUAAUCUUACACAGCUAAAUUACUGAUUAUAUAUUUGCUGAGCUGAUUUAAGGGUUAAAAAAAUUGUAUCAAGAGUUUUAUUUUUUGACUUCAAAGCCUUCUUAAUAAAGCCUCUUUUCUACAUGUGA